AGAAAGCCGCGCACCUCCUCCCGCCAGGCGCUUUCUCGGACGCCUUGCCCAGCGGGCCGCCCGACCCCCUGCACCAUGGACCCCGCUCGCCCCCUGGGGCUGUCGAUUCUGCUGCUUUUCCUGACGGAGGCUGCACUGGGCGAUGCUGCUCAGGAGCCAACAGGAAAUAACGCGGAGAUCUGUCUCCUGCCCCUAGACUACGGACCCUGCCGGGCCCUACUUCUCCGUUACUACUACGACAGGUACACGCAGAGCUGCCGCCAGUUCCUGUACGGGGGCUGCGAGGGCAACGCCAACAAUUUCUACACCUGGGAGGCUUGCGACGAUGCUUGCUGGAGGAUAGAAAAAGUUCCCAAAGUUUGCCGGCUGCAAGUGAGUGUGGACGACCAGUGUGAGGGGUCCACAGAAAAGUAUUUCUUUAAUCUAAGUUCCAUGACAUGUGAAAAAUUCUUUUCCGGUGGGUGUCACCGGAACCGGAUUGAGAACAGGUUUCCAGAUGAAGCUACUUGUAUGGGCUUCUGCGCACCAAAGAAAAUUCCAUCAUUUUGCUACAGUCCAAAAGAUGAGGGACUGUGCUCUGCCAAUGUGACUCGCUAUUAUUUUAAUCCAAGAUACAGAACCUGUGAUGCUUUCACCUAUACUGGCUGUGGAGGGAAUGACAAUAACUUUGUUAGCAGGGAGGAUUGCAAACGUGCAUGUGCAAAAGCUUUGAAAAAGAAAAAGAAGAUGCCAAAGCUUCGCUUUGCCAGUAGAAUCCGGAAAAUUCGGAAGAAGCAAUUUUAAACAUUCUUAAUAUGUCAUCUUGUUUGUCUUUAUGGCUUAUUUGCCUUUAUGGUUGUAUCUGAAGAAUAAUAUGACAGCAUGAGGAAACAAAUCAUUGGUGAUUUAUUCACCAGUUUUUAUUAAUACAAGUCACUUUUUAAAAAAUUUGGAUUUUUUUAUAUAUAACUAGCUGCUAUUCAAAUGUGAGUCUACCAUUUUUAAUUUAUGGUUCAACUGUUUGUGAGACUGAAUUCUUGCAAUGCAUAAGAUAUAAAAGCAAAUAUGACUCACUCAUUUCUUGGGGUCGUAUUCCUGAUUUCAGAAGAGGAUCAUAACUGAAACAACAUAAGACAAUAUAAUCAUGUGCUUUUAACAUAUUUGAGAAUAAAAAGGACUAGCAAAUAAAACUCAUUUUGCAUUUAAAAGUUGGAUUAUAUUUUAGUCCCAAGAAGACAAAGUCGCAGAUUAACAACACUUUAAAAAUAUUACUCCCAUUUUAUUGUGUUAGAUUGCAGUACAAUGAAUGAAUAAGGGGAUUUAUUUAAAAGAUCUUAACUUUCUUGACUGAUUUAAAAAGCUAAUCAAUUUAUUAAAGCCAGAAAUGUUCUCCUCUGGGAAAGCAAUUUCUAUCUAUUUAUCUACCAAUCCCCACUCACAUGUAUAUGUUUGUGUUUACAUAGAGAUAGAUGGUUUUAAGGGUUUUCCUAUUGUUAAAUUAUUUCCUAAGACAUUGUGGGUUGGAGACCACUAAACUUAUAAAAAACCAAGGAAAGUAAAGUUUUUCAAAUGUUUAUACUGUUUAAGGUGUUUAUUUAUAUAAACCAUGCAUGAGAAACCAUGCAUAAAUUUAAUAAUUUAAAUUUCACCAGUAAAUUAUCAUUGAUUAAAUAUGGUCAUACCAAUGAAAUAGGUUUUUUCUUUCUCUGUAAUAAAACAAUUUUUCUAAAUUCUUAUGUUUUCAUAGCAAGAUUAACAUAUUUAAUUACAAAUUAAAUAUGCAAAAUGACAAAUGCGUUUACCUUUUGCUUGAACAAUCUUUCAUUUAAAAAUUUAUCCCAGUUAUUUUGACAAAUAGGUAUAUGCCUGAGAACUUUGAAUGAUGCUGAAAGCUAGAAGCAAACCAGGUACUCUUCAGUCAGGGACUGGUUGAAGAUUUUAUGGAUGAGGAGUUAGCAAAAUAUCUAUAUAUGCAUAUCUUCUGACUCCCAGGAUACAUAAGAAACACAGGGCCUAGAACAGUAUGAAUAAACACACAUAUACACAAACAUCACAGAAGAUACUAAAGAUAUUAAAAAUGUUUACCUAUAGAGGUUUGGAGAGAACAGAGGGGUGGACAGUUGUGGAGAUAAUAUUUGUGUAAAUAUAACUGUGAUAUAGUUUUUAUCUUGGACCAUGUAAAUAUUUGACAUAAUUAAUAAUCAAAAUUAAAUAAAAAAGAAAAAGCA